GGGCAGGCAAGGGCGGCCGAGCGGGCGGCGGGCAUGAGCGGGGCGGGCAGGGCGCUGGCCGCGCUGCUGCUGGCCGCGUCCGUGCUGAGCGCCGCGCUGCUGGCCCCCGGCGGCUCUUCGGGGCGCGAUGCCCAGGCCGCGCCGCCACGAGACUUAGACAAAAAAAGACAUGCAGAGCUGAAGAUGGAUCAGGCUUUGCUACUCAUCCAUAAUGAACUUCUCUGGACCAACUUGACCGUCUACUGGAAAUCUGAAUGCUGUUAUCACUGCUUGUUUCAGGUUCUGGUAAACGUUCCUCAGAGUCCAAAAGCAGGGAAGCCUAGUGCUGCAGCUGCCUCUGUCAGCACCCAGCACGGAUCUAUCCUGCAGCUGAACGACACCUUGGAAGAGAAAGAAGUUUGUAGGUUGGAAUACAGAUUUGGAGAAUUUGGAAACUAUUCUCUCUUGGUAAAGAACAUCCAUAAUGGAGUUAGUGAAAUUGCCUGUGACCUGGCUGUGAACGAGGAUCCAGUUGAUAGUAACCUUCCUGUGAGCAUUGCAUUCCUUAUUGGUCUUGCUGUCAUCAUUGUGAUAUCCUUUCUGAGGCUCUUGUUGAGUUUGGAUGACUUUAACAAUUGGAUUUCUAAAGCCAUAAGUUCUCGAGAAACUGAUCGCCUCAUCAAUUCUGAGCUGGGAUCUCCCAGCAGGACAGACCCUCUCGAUGGUGAUGUUCAGCCAGCAACGUGGCGUCUAUCUGCCCUGCCGCCCCGCCUCCGCAGCGUGGACACCUUCAGGGGGAUUGCUCUUAUACUCAUGGUCUUUGUCAAUUAUGGAGGAGGAAAAUAUUGGUACUUCAAACAUGCAAGUUGGAAUGGGCUGACAGUGGCUGACCUCGUGUUCCCGUGGUUUGUAUUUAUUAUGGGAUCUUCCAUUUUUCUAUCGAUGACUUCUAUACUGCAACGGGGGUGUUCAAAAUUCAGAUUGCUGGGGAAGAUUGCAUGGAGGAGUUUCCUGUUAAUCUGCAUAGGAAUUAUCAUUGUGAAUCCCAAUUAUUGCCUUGGUCCAUUGUCUUGGGACAAGGUGCGCAUUCCUGGUGUGCUGCAGCGAUUGGGAGUGACAUACUUUGUGGUUGCUGUGUUGGAGCUCCUCUUUGCUAAACCUGUGCCUGAACAUUGUGCCUCGGAGAGGAGCUGCCUUUCUCUUCGAGACAUCACGUCCAGCUGGCCCCAGUGGCUGCUCAUCCUGGUGCUGGAAGGCCUGUGGCUGGGCUUGACAUUCCUCCUGCCAGUCCCUGGGUGCCCUACUGGUUAUCUUGGUCCUGGGGGCAUUGGAGAUUUUGGCAAGUAUCCAAAUUGCACUGGAGGAGCUGCAGGCUACAUCGACCGCCUGCUGCUGGGAGACGAUCACCUUUACCAGCACCCAUCUUCUGCUGUACUUUACCACACCGAGGUGGCCUAUGACCCCGAGGGCAUCCUGGGCACCAUCAACUCCAUCGUGAUGGCCUUUUUAGGAGUUCAGUGCUGCCCAGACUGGGUCACCAAACAGGCCUGUCUGACGGAACCCUUGUCACCUUUGUGGAGAAUUCUCUUUGGGCCCUGCCUGGAAGUAAGAGCCACGGAGCCUGCCCAGGCAGGAAAAAUACUAUUGUAUUACAAGGCUCGGACCAAAGACAUCCUGAUUCGAUUCACUGCUUGGUGUUGUAUUCUUGGGCUCAUUUCUGUUGCUCUGACGAAGGUUUCUGAAAAUGAAGGCUUUAUUCCAGUAAACAAAAAUCUCUGGUCCCUUUCGUAUGUCACUACGCUCAGUUCUUUUGCCUUCUUCAUCCUGCUGGUCCUGUACCCAGUUGUGGAUGUGAAGGGGCUGUGGACAGGAACCCCAUUCUUUUAUCCAGGAAUGAAUUCCAUUCUGGUAUAUGUCGGCCACGAGGUGUUUGAGAACUACUUCCCCUUUCAGUGGAAGCUGAAGGACAACCAGUCCCACAAGGAGCACCUGACUCAGAACAUCGUCGCCACUGCCCUCUGGGUGCUCAUUGCCUACAUCCUCUAUAGAAAGAAGAUUUUUUGGAAAAUCUGAUGGCUCCCACUGAGAUGUGCUGCUGGAAGACUCUAGUAGGCCUGCAGGGAGGACUGAAGCAGCCUUUGUUAAAGGGAAGCAUUCAUUAGGAAAUUGACUGGCUGCGUGUUUACAGACUCUGGGGGAAGACACUGAUGUCCUCAAACUGGUUAACUGUGACACGGCUCGCCAGAACUCUGCCUGUCUAUUUGUGACUUACAGAUUUGAAAUGUAAUUGUCUUUUUUCCUCCAUCUUCUGUGGAAAUGGAUGUCUUUGGAACUUCAUUCCGAGGAGAUAAGCUUUAACUUUCCAAAAGGGAAUUGCCAUGGGUGUUUUUCUUCUGUGGUGAGUGAAACAAUCUGAGGUCUGGUUCUUGCUGACCUUGUUGCCCUGCAAACUUCCUUUCCACGUGUACGCGCACACCAACACGAAAUGCCAUCACUCCUACUGCGGCUGCUAUGAAGCUUACUGGUUGUGAUGUGUUAUAAUUUAGUCUGUUUUUUUGAUUGAAUGCAGUUUAAUGUUUCCAGAAAGCCAAAGUAAUUUUCUUUUCAGAUAUGCAAGGCUUUGGUGGGUCCAAAAAAUGUCUAUCACAAGCCAUUUUUUCCUUUUCCUCUCUCGAAAAGUUAAAAUAUCUAUGUGUUAUUCCCAAACCCUCUUACCUAUGUAUCUGCCUGUCUGUCCAUCAUCUUCCUUCCUCCCUAUCUCUGUGUAUCUGGAUGGCAGCCGCUGCCCAGGGGAGUGGCUGUGGGGAGGGCAGGUACUGUCUUUGCCUGUGGGUCCAGCUGAGCCAUCCCUGCUGGGUGAUGCUGGGCAAGACCCUUGGCCCGUCUGGGCCUUGGCUUCCUCACUUGUGAAAUGAGCGGGAAGAUGACUCUCAGUUCCUUCCACCUCUUAGACAUGGUGAGGUAACAGACAUCAAAAGCUUUUCUGAAAUCUUCAGAAGAAAUAGUUCCAUUACAGAAAACUCUUCAAAAUAAAUAGUAGUGAAAACUUUUAAAAACUCUCAUUGGAGUAAGUCUUUUCAAGAUGAUCCUCCACAAUGGAGGCAGCGUUCCUACUUGUCAUCACACAGCUGAAGACAUUGUUUCUUAGGUGUGAAAUCGGGGACAAAGGACAAACAGAGACACACGGCAUUGUUCAUGGGAGGCAUCGUCACCCUCCUGGGUGUUCUGUGGGAAUUUCCUGUGUGAGGAAAACGUGGCCACAGGGUUGUGCUGUACCCACCCUUCCCCGGCGAGAUGGCCCUCGGCCUGUGCCGCUGCUUCCACCCUCGCCACUCCAUGGCAGCUUUUGGUCUGUUUCCGGCUCUGCCCUCUGCCCUGAACUCUCAUCCGGCUUGUACCUGCCUGCUGGACCCCUCCACCUGGAGGCCAGCCCAUGUCUCAGGCCCAGCCCUAGCCUCUUCUCCUCAAAUUCUAAGUGUUUUCUCUUUAGGUUUCCCUGGCUUUGUGAAUGGAUCAUGUGUCUCUAGGUAUAAACCUGACAUCAUCUUUCCACCCGGCUUACCUCCACCAGAUCUCCCCAGUUCUGUCUCCAUCUUCUACCUGCAGCUGCUCUGUUCUCAUGGUCACUGCUGCAUCACUGAGUCUGGACCCUUGUUAUCAUUUUCAAACUGGCCUCCUUCCCUCGUUCCCCACUUCUUAAAGUCACCUGUCCAUUGCCACCAGAUUAAGCUUUCUCCAGCCAGAUCACCUCUCUCUGAGAAACCUCCAUUGACAUGGAAACACCAUUGUCUGGCACACAUACUCACAUACUCACCUUCCCGUCUUGAUCCCCACACAUCUUUCCAGCCUCCCCUCCCACUCCACUCCCUGCUCUCUCCUCCACCUCCCCAUCCUCUUGUCUCCCCUCCCCUCUGAAUCCAGCCCAGCGGGGCUUCUCCUGCCUCCAUCACAUCACAGAAGUACCUCCUGCUUCUGGUUUUAAUUAGAGCCUUCCCCGAUUACAUUUUCCUCUGAAUUUUUUCCUAUCUACAUUUGAUCUGUCAUGUUUAAACCCCCUACUUCUAAGGGAACUUCUCUAAUCUCUUAUCCUCAUCCCCAAAUAGUGUUUUCUUCCUCUGGGUUCUUAUAAUGUUGGUAUCAAUCUCACAGCAUUUAGUGCUUCCUGCCUGGUGUGACAGUUACCUGUGUGCAUGUGCAAUUUCUAAUUUCCCACGCUAGACUGUGAGCUUCCUAAGGCAAGAAUCAUGCCUUGUUGGUUUCUGUAUUCCUCAUGGUGCCAAACACAGUGCCUUCUACAUUGCAGGCGCUGAAUAAACAUUUUUAAAGCAAAAUGAUGUGGAUUUUUAAAAUAAAUAUUUAAGUGCUGGUAAGAUGAGCAUGUAUCCGGGGUGCCCAUGAAAUGUUCUUGGGGCCGUGUGGGGACAGUCGUCAUUCCUCCUCCUGCCACCCUUUUCUUUCAGUGAGUCACUGUGGAUGGUCCCAGCUGUGUCAUCCCAAAGUUCAGCAGGGAAAGCUGAGCUGGGCCUCUCCAGGUGAGUUUUCUAGAAGCAUUUCUCAAACUGUGGGUUACAUCAACUUGGGUGUCUUGAGCUGUAAGGAAGGAACUCCGGAGUCAGCUGGGCUACAGGGGAGCUUCUCUAAGUCCUGCGGGAGGCCAGACCCAGCCUGAGCUUGCUGUUAGCUAGCGGAGGCAGCUGCUGGUGGCCCAGGUGCUCGACACCAGGCAUCCCCUCUCCUCCCACGAAGGGUGUGCCAUAAUCCCCUUCAACAGGAAAUGCUUCCCAGAAGCCUCUCAGCAGCCUCCCCUCCUGUCCUAUCAGCUAGAAGCGCCUCGCUUGUCCCAAGACCAGCAGGGACAGGGAACUGUCCGAGCCCGUGGCUGUGUGGAGGAAGGCGACCCCCAGCACAAGAUUGGUUUCCUUUGGGAAGGGAAGAGGGAGUGUGUUGGGGUAAGGGGUAGAGCAGAGGAAUGGUCAGGGGGCAACAACCGCUGACAGCUGCAACAGGUGCAUGGCAUCUCACAGGGAGGCAGGGAGGUGCGAGCUCCUAAGUAAUGGAGCAAAAAAAUUCUAUUCUGUAGAAUGGGGAGAGAAAAUGUGACAUUUUAAUUUUUUUUUGCAUUUAUAUUCCUAAUUCCUACUUAAAGUGAAUAUACUGCCGCUGUAGAUCAUAAAAUGUAUCUUUUCCAUGGCCAACAAGGGGCAUCUUUUAUAAAUGCAUAAUAACCCAGUUUGUAUCAAAGGGUAUCGACUUAAGUGAAAUUUCAACAUGCUGUUACUUUUUCCUUUUAAUGUAAUUCUGUUUUCCAAAUAAAUGGGGGAGACAAAUGGACUUUGAGUAAAUUUCUUAGCAUAUCAAA